GUCCAGGGAAGGAACACGCCCCCGGUGACAGCCGGUACGGCCCCGGGUUUGGGCAACCUCGAUUACGGGCGGCCUCCAGCCCCGCCAGCAGCGCCCCGCGCCCGCCCGCCCGCGCCCCUGCCGCCCCCCGGUUCCGGCCGCGGACCCCACUCUCUGCCGUUCCGGCUGCGGCUCCGCUGCCGGUAGCGCCGUCCCCCGGGACCACCCUUCGGCUGGCGCCCUCCCAUGCUCUCGGCCACCCGGAGGGCUUGCCAGCUCCUCCUCCUCCACAGCCUCUUUCCCGUCCCGAGGAUGGGCAACUCGGCCUCGAACAUCGUCAGCCCCCAGGAGGCCUUGCCGGGCCGGAAGGAACAGACCCCUGUAGCGGCCAAACAUCAUGUCAAUGGCAACAGAACAGUCGAACCUUUCCCAGAGGGAACACAGAUGGCUGUAUUUGGAAUGGGAUGUUUCUGGGGAGCUGAAAGGAAAUUCUGGGUCUUGAAAGGAGUGUAUUCAACUCAAGUUGGUUUUGCAGGAGGCUAUACUUCAAAUCCUACUUAUAAAGAAGUCUGCUCAGAAAAAACUGGCCAUGCAGAAGUCGUCCGAGUGGUGUACCAGCCAGAACACAUGAGUUUUGAGGAACUGCUCAAGGUCUUCUGGGAGAAUCACGACCCGACCCAAGGUAUGCGCCAGGGGAACGACCAUGGCACUCAGUACCGCUCGGCCAUCUACCCGACCUCUGCCAAGCAAAUGGAGGCAGCCCUGAGCUCCAAAGAGAACUACCAAAAGAAGAACCGAAGAGGCCAGAGUCCUCCGAAGACGCCUGCUUGGAAGUUGAGAUGCUGUUGCUGAAACUGCUAGAAUGCCAGGCAUGCUAUCACCUGCAGCUUUGAGACGUCACGCUGACAGUAUCACAGGAAAACAGCCUUUUGUGGGCCGUCCUCUGUGUGUUCACACCGUGUCGUUUUUAAGCUUUAAAGGAAACUGACAAAAGCUUCUUUUCUCUCUGUCUUGAGCUUCACUGCGUAUUCUUAACCAUGUGGAGCUGGGAGCUAACGCAUCACAGCCAACUGUAUCUGGAGUGCAUUUGCUCAUAUAGCCCUUAUUUUAUUUUUUAGUCUUAUUUUUAGUUUCCUUUGAAUAUAAUAAUAAAAAAAAAAAACCCAAUCAUUGAAUUCUUAGCUUCAGCCAAUAUAGUGUGAGGUUAGACAUAUUGCAGCCCAAGGGAGAAUUUCUGCUUGCAAGCUGGUCAGCCUGUUUGCAGCUGACAGAUGUAACCUGCCCUAGGGCAAGAGAAAGUCUCAAGGGAGCUUUUAAUUUCUUAAUAUUGAAAUGAGCACAACCUUUAUUGUCUUAAUCAGUGAAUAAAAAAAAUAAAGUUGCUAAGUCUCAUUUUUUAAACAUGGCGUAAGAGGAUUUUAAGAAAUUACAAUUGCUUUUUAAGCUGCUGUUGAAAGUUAAUUUUCUCUGUGUUCAGGAAGAUUCUGCCAGCAGCUCCUAGCUAGGUAGUCAUAUUCCAGUUAAGCAAAACUUUCCCAGGGGUGGCGAACAGCCCUGUUCUGUGGACACCGCCCCUGGGAAGGGAAAGGGUGUGUGUCGUCCACAGAGUGGUUUUACUUUGUCCUUGAACUUGGUUUUUAUCACGUUUCAUAAACUCAGAAUACAGGAGUACUCAUUUAAAAUUACAGCAGAAAUCUUCUGAUGCAAACUGCAUUCUUUUAGAAUAUAUGAUACUUUAGGCAAGGGCCGUAUUAACAUUUUUUUCGCCAUUCAUAAAGAAGGGAUUGAUGAAUGAUAGUGAAUAGCCCCUAUACAGUCAUAAGGAAAAUGUUUCCGUUUUUAGUCUGAACAAAUAAUUGUAUAUGAAAAAAUCUGAUGUAUUGCAGCUAGUCGUUCUUAAGUGUUUCUUAAUUUAAUCCAAAUUUGAACCACGUUUCUUUAAAUUAAAAGUUCCUCAAUUACAAGGGCCACAGGCUUGUCAAUUCUGGUUCCCUGGUACUUUGUGUAAUGCCCGAAUAGGGACACAGUAAAUGUGUGCUGAACCAACUGAAAAAGUUGCUUUCAGAGCUACAUGGGAAUGAAUGUGGACCUGCAGAGAUAUUACAUGUGAUAUAAACUAUCGAACAUGAUGUUCCAGGUAUAGAACGAAGAUGCUCAACGGGAGCAUACCAGAAUCAUGGGACAGGGGUUACGCGUUUGAAGCCAAAGCAUAACUUUGGAAUAUUUAGAGAACCCUCAAAAUUCAACAAUACAAGCAAAUCACCUGAUUAAAAAAUGGACACGAGAUUAGAACAGACACUUCACCAAAGAAGUCCCUUCACCUACAGGAUGCCUUCGUAUACAGAAGGCAAAUAGGAACGUUAAAAGGUGCCCAGCAUCAUUAGUCAUUGGAGAAAUGCAGAUGACAGCCACGUUGUGAUGCUACUCUACAGCAGUUAGAAUGAGCAAAUCAAAGAAUCGUGACAAUACCAAGUCCUGGGAAUGACACAGAGCAAUGGGAACUCUCAUGCAUUGCAGGGGACUGAGGUGGGGAGCACAAAGUGGCAUGAUCAGUUUGGAAAACCAUUGGAAAUUUCCCAUCAUUUAAUAUACUUCCACCUACUGUGAGCCAGCAAUCCCAGUCCUAGAUUUUUACCUACGAGAAAUAAGACGACACAAAAACCCAUUCCCAAAUGUUUACAGCAGCUUUGUUCAUAAUAGCCAGAAACAGGAAACAACCUAAGUGGCCUUCAGUUGGGAAAUGGAAACACCACACUGAGGAAUGCGUAUGCCCAGGAAGGCCCUGAUCUCGCCUGUGGCUGCCAUGAGGCCCUGCACAAGGGAAGAGAAGAAGAGAAGGCCGAGUGGAGAACCGUGGGGUCCCUGAAGCUUCCUGUGCUCUAGCGCACACACAGCCCUCAGCAAAGGUAGGAGUCUGGUGCUUCCAGGCCUGUAAGGAAUUCGGUGCCUAACCAUUCGGUGAUAAUUAGCUAACCACACUGAGACUUCAAUGGCCACACCUGAAAGAGAAGACAGACUUUACAGAAUUAGUCCAAGAAAGUCACUGAACAAAGGAACAGCAGCAGCAGAAGCAACACCACACUGUGGGGCAGGACAUCGGAUUUCCAGAGUUGCCACAUUAUUUUUUAAAUUGUCUGAUUUUCAAGAAAAAAAUAUGUAACAAAGAAACAUGACGGUAUCCGUUACUAAACAAAGACUUUAAAUCUGCUGUUAUAAAGGUGCACCAAGAACUAAAGGAAACUGAAAAAAUUAAAAGAAAAUGUUAGAGUAAUGCCUCAACAAAUAAAGAAUAUCAGUAAGGAGAGAGAUAUUAAAAAAAAAAAAAAAGAACUAAGUAGAAAUUCAAAGAUACAAUAACUUUUUAAAAAAUCGCCAGAAGGGCUGAGUUGGCGGAAGAAAGAAUGAAACUGGAAGAUAAGUCAAUUGAUAUUAUCCAGUCUGAGGAACAGAAUUUAAAAUGGGGGAAAAACGGUGAUGGUUACAUAACCUUGAAAAUAUUUUGAAAACCACUGAAU